AUUAGGGCUCUGGUGGCGGCGGUGGCGGACACUUGGGGUCUGGACGCAACGGCGGCGGGAGCAUGAACGCCCCUCCAGCCUUCGAGUCGUUCUUGCUCUUCGAGGGCGAGAAGAUCACCAUUAACAAGGACACCAAGGUACCCAAUGCCUGUUUAUUCACCAUCAACAAAGAAGACCACACACUGGGAAACAUCAUUAAAUCACAACUCCUAAAAGACCCGCAAGUGCUAUUUGCUGGCUACAAAGUCCCCCACCCCUUGGAGCACAAGAUCAUCAUCCGAGUGCAGACCACGCCGGACUACAGCCCCCAGGAAGCCUUUACCAACGCCAUCACCGACCUCAUCAGUGAGCUGUCCCUGCUGGAGGAGCGCUUCCGGACGUGCCUGCUUCCCCUUCGCCUUCUGCCGUGAUUGUCAGUUUCCUGAGGCCUCCCCAGCCACGCUUCCUGUACAGCCUGCAGAACUGUGAGUCAAUUAAACCUCUUUUCUUCAUAAA